AUGGAGUCUCACUCUGUCGCCCAGGCUAAAGUGCAGUGGCACGAUCUUGGCUCACUGCUACUUCCGCCUCCAGGGUUCAAGCAAUUCUCCUGCCUCAGCCUCCUAAGUAGCUGGGAUUAUAGGCAUGCACCACCAUGCCCAGUUAUGCUGAUAGAAGUGGACAAUGAAUUCAAUGAGGGGACGGAGAAGAUUUUUAGUGGAGAUGGUGUUUCGCCAUGUUGGCCAGGCUGGUCUAGAACCCCUGGCCUCAGAUGA